AGGAUUAGGGUUAGGGGUUAGAGCUGAGAGGGAGAAGAGAUCAGAAAGGGAAGAAAAGGUGUAGGACACCCUGCUCUGGGGAUGAGAAGGGAAGCUGAGAAUGCCAUUGACUUGUCACCAAAGGAGAAACUGAAGUUAGAGAGUCAGGGAGUAUUUGGAGAAGCGUGGACAGUUAUCUAGUAGGUUCUGGGUAAAGCAAGAGUUCAGUGGCCGAAUGAAGAGCUCCACCUAAGCGGGUCUGAAUGUCUUAGGAGGAUUCCAGGCCUCAGGCUCCUGCAUAAUUCUACGGCAAGGGCAAGAAGUUGUAAAACAGGUUUUUGAGCAAAAUAGCCACAUAGACUAAUUUGGCCUGGCAUUGUCCUAACUCUUAAUACCUCUCUCUCUCUGCUCCUCAGCACCCAAAGCCCACCCAUAUGUACCAACCAACUGCACCUUCCUCUACCGGCCUACUCUUCAUCUACCCUGGGUCCCAUCCUCCCGUCUCCUCCUCCUCCUCCCUCAGAGCUCCACCUAAGCCUGUCUUCAAAGGCAAUGACCUGCAUACAGAAUUAGGCCAUCUCUUCUACUCUCCACCCCAUCAGCUCUCAAAUUUCCACCAAAACUUAUCUCAUCUUAUAGUUGUCAGGAAAGCAACUUGAAUAAUGAUGACUUCAUGUGUUAACUACCUCAGGUCCUUUACAUGGUAAAGAAGGCACUCAUUACCUCAAACACCACAGACAUUCAGAAUUGUGUUUUCUGAAGAAAUUUUAGACCUUUUUUGUGGUGCAUCUCAAAGUAUACAAAGCACACACUUCAUAUUAACAUAUCAUGUUAAGUAGAUGCUAGAGGAAAGAUCCAGUUUUAUCACCAGUGUCUUAACCACUGUGUUGUACCCUCGGCAUGAGCUUACCUUUGAAGAGCAAUCUACAAGAGGAGUUUACCUGGAGUAACUCAAGAUGAUUUUGAUGUUGCAGUUUUAAAUUUCACUUUGACUUGAGCUGGGAAAUCCUUUGGCCUAUUAUACCAUGGAUGCUAAAAAUGGUUCUAACUGAAAACCCAAACCAAGAAAUAGCAACAAGUCUAGAAUUCUUACUACUACAAAACUCACCUGGAUCCCUAAGGGCACAGCAAAGAAUGAGCUAUUACGGCAGCAGCUAUCAUAUUAUCAAUGCGGACGCAAAAUACCCAGGCUACCCGCCAGAGCACAUUAUAGCUGAGAAGAGAAGAGCAAGAAGACGAUUACUUCACAAAGAUGGCAGCUGUAAUGUCUACUUCAAGCACAUUUUUGGAGAAUGGGGAAGCUAUGUGGUUGACAUCUUCACCACUCUUGUGGACACCAAGUGGCGCCAUAUGUUUGUGAUAUUUUCUUUAUCUUAUAUUCUCUCGUGGUUGAUAUUUGGCUCUGUCUUUUGGCUCAUAGCCUUUCAUCAUGGCGAUCUAUUAAAUGAUCCAGACAUCACACCUUGUGUUGACAACGUCCAUUCUUUCACAGGGGCCUUUUUGUUCUCCCUAGAGACCCAAACCACCAUAGGAUAUGGUUAUCGCUGUGUUACUGAAGAAUGUUCUGUGGCCGUGCUCAUGGUGAUCCUCCAGUCCAUCUUAAGUUGCAUCAUAAAUACCUUUAUCAUUGGAGCUGCCUUGGCCAAAAUGGCAACUGCUCGAAAGAGAGCCCAAACCAUUCGUUUCAGCUACUUUGCACUUAUAGGUAUGAGAGAUGGGAAGCUUUGCCUCAUGUGGCGCAUUGGUGAUUUUCGGCCAAACCACGUGGUAGAAGGAACAGUUAGAGCCCAACUUCUCCGCUAUACAGAAGACAGUGAAGGGAGGAUGACGAUGGCAUUUAAAGACCUCAAAUUAGUCAACGACCAAAUCAUCCUGGUCACCCCGGUAACUAUUGUCCAUGAAAUUGACCAUGAGAGCCCUCUGUAUGCCCUUGACCGCAAAGCAGUAGCCAAAGAUAACUUUGAGAUUUUGGUGACAUUUAUCUAUACUGGUGAUUCCACUGGAACAUCUCACCAAUCUAGAAGCUCCUAUGUUCCCCGAGAAAUUCUCUGGGGCCAUAGGUUUAAUGAUGUCUUGGAAGUUAAGAGGAAGUAUUACAAAGUGAACUGCUUACAGUUUGAAGGAAGUGUGGAAGUAUAUGCCCCCUUUUGCAGUGCCAAGCAAUUGGACUGGAAAGACCAGCAGCUCCACAUAGAAAAAGCACCACCAGUUCGAGAAUCCUGCACGUCGGACACCAAGGCGAGACGAAGGUCAUUUAGUGCAGUUGCCAUUGUCAGCAGCUGUGAAAACCCUGAGGAGACCACCACUUCCGCCACACAUGAAUAUAGGGAAACACCUUAUCAGAAAGCUCUCCUGACUUUAAACAGAAUCUCUGUAGAAUCCCAAAUGUAGUCCUAAAUUGCAAUUAUGAGGGCUACCACUGAAUCAUUUUAUCUUUCAGCCAAUCAAGUCGUUGUAAACGUGGCUUUUUUGAAAGUGUUAUGGCUAUGUUUUAUGAUGAUGCUGGGUAAGUAGAGUAAGUUAAACUUGGUAAAAGAUAAUCUAAAAAUUCCAUAGUUCUCAGUUAUUAAAAUUUUUCUUGUUCGCCAAUUUUGUAUUAAGAAUGCUAUUAAGCCUAAUUGAUUAAAAUUUAUCUUUUUUAUUAUCUUACAUGCUUGUAUCUUCAGUUGGAGGUGUAGUAUUCAAAAACGGGGAAUGAAGGCAGGAAGGAGGCUGGAAUAAAUAAAAAUAAAAAUAGACAAGUAAGACAGCAUAAAUAAUACAUUUUUAAACAUGUCAACAUUGAUAAUACAAUGAAGAUUUACCAUAAAAAGUAUCAUAUCUAACCAAGAUAUGCAAAAGAUGCAUUCAGUAAGCUGUAACGUUGAGAAAUGUAACUGUGAAAUCAGCUCACCAGUUCAAGUCACUAGGUUUGCCACUUGGACCGUCUUGGUUUCAGCGAGCAUAGCGAGUGGCUGUAAGAAAUUGUCCAUGCCACCAAUUCCACUGCUACUUGCCCAGGUAGUGAUCAGUGAGAGUUAGAAGCAAUUUUUUCUCUAACCGAUGAGGCAGAAGAAAAGUUAACAGUAUUUAAAGCAGCAUUUCUCUCUUAACGUUCCUGGGAGACUCCAACAAAUGGAGACCAGAAACAAGGCAACCACGACCUUGCUAGGUUCUCUGAGGAGGGGACUUUCUAUGUUCACGUCCCACCUUCUUCGAGGACAUGACCAAGGGACAGGAUCAUACAGAUGAGGUGAGGGGAUGGUUAGCAGCGAUAAACAUUCUCAGACCCUUGGAGAGAAACCGUUGCUAGCUUGCUGGUCCCGAAAGAUUGCAACUUUGGCUGCUACAGAAAGGAUAGAACCUUUUUGGGGGGAGGGUGGGGAGGGAGAUAUUUAUUUGUGCCCAGAAGCAGUUAUGUAUGCUUCUUGUCUUGGUUACUGUACAAGAUACAAAUGACUCGAGUUGUGGAUUGCAAGAAACUCUUUUAUUAAACUUGGAACAACCAUUUAAAUGAAGGAUUUUGUGAGAUAGAAUUCAAUUAAAGCGAUUUGAAUGCACAGUAAGUGGAUAAUCUGAGUACAAUGAAAUUUCUUAAGUUUUAGAACAUGAGAUAAAGUUGUAUACUCUACUUUCAUGUUAAAAUGUUAAUCAUGAUUACUUUAAGCCCACAUCCACUGAGUAAAGAGUCACUUUAAACUUUAUAAAUCAAAGAGAUAUUAGGAACAUUCAGAAUUAUUUGUGUUUUGUUUUUGUUUUACAUUGUUGCUGCACUGGCAAUAAGUAUGUGGCACUGUUUUUAUUUGUUUAUGUUAUUUAAAUACACACCCAGACACACACACACACAGUUUUUGCUUUUUCUGGAAAAUCUUUCUUUCUCUUCUCUCUCCAUGAAAAUUAAAACACACAAGUGAAUGAAGUAAUUACAUAGUCCAAGAUUAGAAAUACAAGUAAAAUAUAUAGGUAUAGGUAGAUAGAGUGCCUUUCUGUUUCUUUUCUUUUCUUUUUUCUUUUUUUGUUCUUCCUUCCUUUCUUCCCUCCUCCCCCUCAUCCUUCCCUUUCUCCUUCUUUUCCCUUUUUUUUUUUUUUUUGACCUGGGAGUAAUAAAGUUACUUUUUAAAUGCACGUAUGCAAUCUUUUAUUCCUCUUGUUUUAUGGAUAAGAGAUUUGUUCAGGUCAAAAGUUGCAAAACUGUUCUGAAGCUUAAUAUUAGAGACCCAAGUAAGAUUGUUUUUAGUCUUGCUUGAGGAAUGCACACUCCAUUUAAAAAAUUGUGCGCUCUGUAGAUUUGGAUUUUACAGCAGCAAUUACUUGGCUAAAUUAGAGUACUGCAAUCUUGUAAGUAGAAAACAGCCACCAUGACAAUAAACAAAAACACUUAAAAAUAUUUUUAGCUUGUUUUACCUACAUCUAGUUUCAUUUCAUCUUGCUUUGCUUUGUUGACUCUGCUACCGCUGAUGUUUGCCUUGUCAAUAUCAGAAUAGGGGCAUCAGUGUCCCGUGAAAUACAUUUUGUUGUGCUAUGAGCCUCUGUAAUCAAAUGCUUGUACUCAGAAGAGAGUGUAAAAUCAGCAUUUCUAUGUAACAUAUAUCUCUAAUUAUCUGUGUAAUUUUAUAACAUACUUUGACAACCCCAGUGAGUUACUUAAUAAUAAAGAUCUUAAAAUAAUGCAAAAA